ACAUAGCCAGUGGGUCUGAGCUGACUUUUCUUCCCAAGCCUGUGUGAUCCCCAAAACCCUUGGCUGCCCCCACUCUGCCCCCCGCCUCCCAGCCCUUCCAGCUGCAGCCUUUUCACUCAUUCCACCACCACUCAGCUCUGAGUGGCUACGCUGGCGGGCUCUCUGCUUUGCGUCGGAGACAUCACAGUGAGCAAAGGCAGAUAUGUUUUAUGUGCCCUUGAAGAAUCUCCCAGACAAACGUGUCAUUGCAGUCGGAGCCAAAUGGCCGGGGCAGGUGGCACAGAUGAAUGCCGGGCAGAGGAGCCUGCAGACUGGGGUCCCCUUAAAGGCAGAGUGAAUCUCAGAUUCAUCUUAGUCCCUUCCUGGGGUCUUGUUCAGGACCCUGCAUCCAGUAGAUGCUCAACAAAUGUCAACAUAGGAAUCCAGGUCCCAUCCUCUCCUCACUCAAGGGAUCCAAGGCUGCCUCUUCCUCUUCCGUAGUGGUGUGGCUUUGCAGAAGUCACUUAAGCUCUCUAAUCCUCCUCCUCAGAGUGCCAGACUGCAGCUGCCACAUGAAGAGAGAGAGGGUCUCCUAUGUUUCCUAGGCCUGUCUUGAACUCCCGGGCUCAAGCGAUUCUCCUGCCUCAGCCUCCCAACAUGCUGGAUCACAGGCAGUGGCCACCUCGCCUGGCCAGUUUUCCCUUUACAAAAACUGGAAUGCUGAGCCGGGCCACAUCAGUCUUGGCUGGACUCACUGCCCACCUCUGGGACCUUGGCGGUGGGGCGGGAAGGAGGACCUCAAAGGCUCAGCGAGUCCACCCCCAGCCCAGCCACCAGCGCCAGCCUCCUCCUCCGCAACACCCAGGCCCUUAUCAGGAAAGGAUUUGGGUUGGUGGGGAGGGGUGGGGGGAAGUUGGAGGCCUCAGGCUCAGCAAGGUGGGUCGGAGAGAUAGGGAAGUGGGGAGGGGGCUGCGGGCCCCUGCUGGGCGGGGGAGGGCAAUGGGAGGGAUGCCCAGAAUGGGCACGGUGGGGGACUUUGGCCAAGCUCUGUCCUCGCUGGCCUGGACCUCAACAUGUUUCCAGGACUUCUGCCUCCCAUCCUUGCCAGGCAAGUUGCCUGCACCUUUAAUUAGCAAGCAGCAGUUUCUCUCCAAUUCAUCACGGUCGCUGUUUAAUUAGCCGAGCCCAGGGCGCCCCCACCCCCAGCUCUGCCUGCCUGUCCUACCAAGGCCACCACCACCUCAGGGUGUCCCCUGUUACCACCCCCCACAAUCAUUCUGCUCCCCAGAGUGGGGGAUGGGCCCGGCACGCCCAGCUGAAACCUCAAGGAGAUUCUGGGCACCGGCGCUUGUAUUCAAGGCAUUCAGCAAACAUGAUUAGGGACCGAGGCUGUGCCAGGCUGGCUCUGGGUAGAACCCCGGCCGGACAUGCGGGGCAGGCUCUGGUCCUGUCCAGCUGCUGGAGAAUGGCUUCUCCCUUGGGAGGCGCUGGCACAUCUCUCUGGCUUGGUCCCUGAGUGCUGGGAGGAGGCUGCAGUACUCCUGUGUGUCACUCCCACCCCACAUCCGGAAAGGGACACCAUGUCUUCCUCUUCCUCUCUCUUCCAGAGCCCAGAAAGCUCCUCUGAGAAUGCUGGACCUCAGGACAGGGGCCCAUGCUCUGCACCCGGCCCUCAGCAGCCAGAUCCUAGAGGCCCAGUCCAAGCUGUGGGCCAAGGGAGCGGGGCGGGCUGAGGCCUGCUUUGUGUCGGCAGGGUCUGGGGAAUUGGGAGCACUGGCGGGAGCCCAUGGUCCGGGGCCGAACCAGCCCCCUUCUGUUUCCCUGAAGAAGGGUGAGGCUGAGGGCCCUCGGAACAGAGCCCCUGUGUCAUUCUGUGCAGGGCCGGGAUAGCCACUAGUCACUGUGGGCAGAAGCAAGAAGCAGAGGCUCAGGCUCCAUCCCAAGCCUGUGCUCCUGCUGGGCUGUGGGAGGUGUGACCCUUCCACUGUUUCGUAGACUGAGAACAUGGAGGGACUGGCAUUUGCUGUGUUACCCUGUGGUGCCAUCAGCGUGUUGUGACAGGGGCAGGAGGAGUGUGCUAGAACCCACCCACUCUGGUACUGCCCAUCUCUGUGGCCUUGGGCCAGCCACCAAACCGUACCAUGCCUUAGUUCCCCUAUGAUUCAUAGCUGCUUCAUGGGCUGAUGUGAGGAUUAAACAGCUUACUAUGUGUUGGGUCUGGUUUUGUUUGGCUUUGUUUUGUUUUUUGAGACAAGGUCUCACUCUGCUGCUCAGGCUGGAGUGCAGUGGUGCAAUCACAGCUCACAGCAGGCUCCACCUCUCAGGCUCAAGCGAUCCUCCCAUCUCAGCCUCCCUGAGUCUCGCUCUUUUGCCCAGGCUGGAUGGAGUGCAGUGGCGUGAUCUCAGCUCGCUGCAACCUCCACCUUCCGGGUUCAAGUGAUUCUCCUAUCUCAGCCUCCUGAGUAGCUGGGAUUACAGACUCCAGCAUAACCUUCUCCAGGAAGCUUUUCCAGAGCCCCCAGGCUAGGAACCUCCCCCCAACCCCUGAACUCAAGCCCCAGCAGCCCGUGCCUGCGCCAUCUCCAUCAGAGCUGCAUCUCUCUGGGUCUCUGGGUAACAAGUGCCAUUUCUUUGUUGUUUUCUGUGUCCCCCAAGGACAAAGCUCAGGCUGGAUUCAUCUCGGAAUUCCCAACACCGGGGUAGAACUGGCUCAUUUCAAUUUCAGUCAAUGUUUGUUGAGGAAAGGAGUGAAGAGUUGGACACAUGAAUGAACGCAUGAAACAGUCCGGAGUGGGGAAGCUGAAGCUCAGGCAUCAGGAUCCGGGAGAAGCAUCCAGUCCAGGCGGACGGGGUGGAAGGUUCAGAGCAGGGGCCCCAAGUCAGGAGUAGGGAGGCAGACGGCAAGACCUCCUUCCAUGAAAGGAGGCUGGGACCAGGGGACCAGGUAGUGCAACGCGGUGAGGGGGCUGUCAGGGCGACUGGCCGGAGGAGUCAGAGGCAGGAGGCACCACCAGGUUACAGACAAGGACCUUCUACAAGAGGGAAACGUGUCAUGGGCUCUGGAGCCCCUGUCCAGGUUCAAAUUGUGACCCUGUGCCAGGGACAGCUUCUUUGUGCCUCAGUUUUUCCCAUAAAAUGAGGAUAAUAAUACUUCAUUCAUGCCUUUUUUUCCCCUCAACAAACAUUUGUUGUAUGUCUGCUGUGGGCCCAGGACAGGAGGCUGAGAAGGAGCUGACCACAGUGGUCACACAGCCAAGCCCUGCUGCUGAGAUCUGACCCCAGUUCGCCUGUCACAAGUUCUAUCUGUGCCUCGUUGUCUGCCUCCUGGGGCUGUUAUGAGGGCUGAAGAAGGGGCAGGCACAGAGGAGACACUUACUAUAUGAUCAUUGUCCUCCUAGAGUAUCAUCACCAUCAGGUGGACUUCAGUGGCCAUCCCAGGCCUCCACGGAUCAACCACAAGAUCUUGGAGAAUGUCCUUACCCUCCAAGCCUCAGUUUACCUUUAGGGUGACCAACCAUCCUGGUUUGUCCAAAACUGAGGGUUUUCCUGGCACAGUCCCAGGCAAACUGGGAUGGUGAGUCACUGAUAUAGUUUGACUCUGUGUCCCCACCAAAUCUCACCUUGAAUUUUAAUAAUCCCUAGGUGUCAAGAGCAGGACCAAGUAGAGAUAAUUGAAUAAUGGUGGCAGUUUCCCCCAUGCUGUUCUCAUGAUAGUGAGUGAGUUCUCACGAGAUCUGAUGGUUUUAUAAGCAGCUUCCCCCUUUGCUCAGUAUCACUCUCCCUCCUGCCGCCCUGUGAAGAGCUGCCUUCCACCAUGAUUGUAAGUUUCCUGAGGCCUCCCCAGCCACGCAGAACUGUGAGUCAAUUAAACCUCUUUUCUUUAUAAAUUACCCCAGUCUCGGGCAUUUCUUCACAGCAGCGUGAGAACAGACUAAUCCCGUCACCCUGGUUUCCUCAUCUCUAACACAGGGACCACCUGCCUCCCAGGGCUGUUGUGCAGAACAGAAAUAAGCCUAUGGAAAAGGCAGAAAACCAUGGAGCCAGAAUUCUAGAUCUGGUUACAUGAAUACUAAAGACUUUUGCAUGCCAUGGAAUUCUAGGCAUGAAAAAGAACGAGGCGGUCCCGUGUACUGCUGUGGAAGAAGCUCUGAGAUACAUGUUUUUUUUGUGAAAAAGGCCAGAUACAGCGCACUUUGUGGGGAGCGCUUCUGUUAGUACCAAGGAGGGGGCAGGAACACACGUGCAUGUGCUCCAGUGCGCACAUGGGUUCUCCCGGGCGGGGACUGGGGGCUGAGGAGAAAAGACUUGUUUUUCACUGUACAUCCCUUUGCUUUGUUUGAAUUAUUUUACCCCUUUGUUUUCAGUAGCUGGCCGAAAAACUUCCCAAGCUUCCAUGUGUCAAAAAGAACUCACUGAACGAGAUUUAAAGGCCAAAGUUAGGGAGUAGGAAAUGUGUCUAGCUCAGGGCCCAGCAUCUAAGGAGUGCUCCAUGAAAGGCCUUCUCCCCUCUCCCACUCCUGACCUUGCUGACUGCUGGGAGUGCAGGGGCACAGACGGGCUGUUGCCUCCCCCAGUGCGGUAUUUGUGAGGCUCAAAUGCAAGCCCAGGCUGGGGAGACUGCUCUGGGUUCCACGCGGCAUCCUGCCUAAGCCCUGGGGGUCCUAGAGGUCACUGGCUCCCUUCUCUGCCUGCAUGUCUCAGGUCGCCCUCUGGCCAAUUCUGAAGUCCUGCCCUGCCUCAAGGAGCAGAGGUGGCAGAGGUGGGCCCACCGCACAGGGUAAAUGUCCCGGUGUCACAUACCUCCAGAUUGCAGGGACCUGCGUAUGCUACUGCUGCUGUGGAAACCAGCUCUCUCUGGCUCUGGCCUUGGGGAGAGGGAGCCACAGUGGAUUUAGGAAGAGUCUCCAGAUGUAGCUUGAGACUACCAAACAGGCCUGACCCCCACAGACCCUGCCUCUUAUGAGCGCCCAGACUGAGCCCUGCUUCAGGCUCCCAGCCAUGUGGCCAGCUGCUUUUCUUCUUUAAUUUUUAGCAUCAGACGAAUAUUUCAGGAAAAUAUUCUCAUUGUAAAAUCUCAAACAUUAAUAAAAUGUAGUGAAUAAAAGGCCAUGUAAUUCCUCUUUA